AGCUCGUUUGGAAGACCUGGGUAUAGGUGGUCGUCUCCUCGGCUCCGAGUCCCUGCAGCAGCUGAGGUGCCUGUGUCUCUCUGGUUCCCAGUGGCCGCCAUCAUGCUCUCCUCCACACUCAGGGUGGCUGUGGUGUGCGUGAGCAAUGUCAACAGGAGCAUGGAGGCCCACAGCAUCCUCAGGAGAAAAGGGCUAAGUGUCCGGUCUUUUGGAACUGAAUCUCAUGUGAGGCUACCAGGACCAAGACCCAAUCGUCCUGUAGUUUACGAUUUUGCAACAACAUAUAAGGAGAUGUACAAUGACCUCCUCAGGAAAGAUAGAGAACGCUACACCCGCAACGGAAUCUUACACAUCUUGGGAAGAAAUGAGAGAAUCAAGCCCGGUCCAGAAAGAUUUCAGGAGUGCACUGAUUUCUUUGAUGUCAUCUUCACCUGUGAGGAGAGUGUCUAUGACACAGUGGUGGAAGAUCUGUGUUCCAGAGAACAGCAGACCUUUCAGCCUGUGCACGUGAUCAACAUGGACAUCCAAGAUACCCUGGAAGAUGCCACCCUGGGAGCUUUCCUCAUCUGUGAGAUUUGCCAGUGCCUGCAGCAGUCAGACGACAUGGAAGACAAUCUGGAAGAGCUGCUGUUGCAAAUGGAGGAGAAGGCAGGAAAAAGCUUUCUUCACACCGUCUGCUUCUACUGAACAUCUGGGCUGGCUUUGUCCCCUUCCUCAGUAAGAACUUAGGCAUGGGACUUUAGUCCGGAUUUAUUGUGAGAAGCAUCUGCAAAGACCUUCCACUGAGUACUGUUUGUGUGACUUUUGUACACAUCACCUGGAAAGAGACUAUUACCAAGAAAAUAUUUUAUGGGAAAUGAGAAGGACUAACAUUUUUAAAAGCACUGAAAAAUGGUUGGCAUUGUGCUAGGUGCAUUACAUGGCAUAACUAAUUUCAUGCUUAUAUCAUUCUACAAGAAAGCUAGCCCACCAUGACGCCAUUUUCCAGAUGAGCAAACCGAGCUGAUAAUGGACUGCUGGAAAAAUGAUUUGUUUAAGGGUAUUCAGCAGAUAAAUAACAUUGUAUAGAUAAGCACCUUUUAAAUAAACUUCCUUUUCUCAA